UGCUCUAAACAUGUAGAUAGUUGCCAAACAUGUAAGUGAAUAUUUAUUUCUGAAUGCCAUGUCAUUUUACUUUCUCUUAAGGGAAGUCAACAUUAUUACAUGAACAUUUCAGAUGUCAUCUCCUUUGAUAUUUUGGUUUCAGCCAUGAAAACAGGAAAUCAAAGUUUUGGGACAGAUUUUCUACUUGUUGGUCUUUUCCAAUAUGGCUGGAUAAACUCUCUUCUCUUUGUCGUCAUUGCCACCCUCUUUACAGUUGCUCUGACAGGAAAUAUCAUGCUGAUCCACCUCAUUCGACUGAACACCAGACUCCACACUCCAAUGUACUUUCUGCUCAGUCAGCUCUCCAUCGUUGACCUCAUGUACAUCUCCACCACAGUGCCCAAGAUGGCAGUCAGCUUCCUCUCACAGAGUAAGACCAUUAGAUUUUUGGGCUGUGAGAUUCAAACGUAUGUGUUCUUGGCCCUUGGUGGAACUGAAGCCCUUCUCCUUGGUUUUAUGUCUUAUGAUCGCUAUGUAGCUAUCUGUCACCCUUUACAUUAUCCUAUGCUUAUGAGCAAGAAGAUCUGCUGCCUCAUGGUUGCAUGUGCAUGGGCCAGUGGUUCUAUCAAUGCUUUCAUACAUACAUUGUAUGUGUUUCAGCUUCCAUUCUGUAGGUCUCGGCUCAUUAACCACUUUUUCUGUGAAGUUCCAGCUCUACUAUCAUUGGUGUGUCAGGACACCUCCCAGUAUGAGUAUACAGUCCUCCUGAGUGGACUUAUUAUCUUGCUACUACCAUUCCUAGCCAUUCUGGCUUCCUAUGCUCGUGUGCUUAUUGUGGUAUUCCAGAUGAGCUCAGGAAAAGGACAGGCAAAAGCUGUUUCCACUUGUUCCUCCCACCUGAUUGUGGCAAGCCUGUUCUAUGCAACCACUCUCUUUACCUACACAAGGCCACACUCCUUGCGUUCCCCUUCACGGGAUAAGGCGGUGGCAGUAUUUUACACCAUUGUCACACCUCUACUGAACCCAUUUAUCUACAGCCUGAGAAAUAAGGAAGUGACGGGGGCAGUGAGGAGACUGUUGGGAUAUUGGAUAUGCUGUAGAAAAUAUGACUUCAGAUCUCUGUAUUGAUUGAGCAUUAACAACAUAAAAAGCUGUUCCUGAAAACUAUCUGGAAA